GUUUUGGGCUGCGGUUGGAGGGCCGCAGUUGCAGUCAGGGUCCGCCAGCUCGGGGCCAGCGCAUGGGGCUGCUGAGACCGCUCCGGACGUGCGAAGCGUUCGCGGUGCGGUAGGAAGCUGAAGUCUUCAGCAGAACCCUGACCUAGGUAGGGAGUCUCAAUGGCCCUGGGUGAAGAAAAGGCAGAAGCGGAAGCAUCUGAAGACACAAAGGCCCAGUCCUAUGGGAGAGGGAGCUGCAGGGAGCGGGAGCUGGACAUCCCAGGGCCCAUGAGUGGGGAGCAGCCCCCACGCCUGGAAGCUGAGGGAGGGCUCAUCUCCCCUGUAUGGGGGGCAGAAGGGAUACCUGCCCCUACUUGCUGGAUUGGGACUGACCCUGGCGGCCCCUCUAGAGCCCACCAGCCACAGGCCAGUGAUGCCAACAGAGAGCCCGUAGCUGAGAGGUCUGAGCCUGCACUCAGUGGCCUGCCUCCUGCCACCAUGGGGUCUGGAGACCUUCUGCUCUCCGGGGAAAGCCAGGUGGAGAAGACCAAGCUUUCUUCCUCCGAGGAGUUCCCUCAGACUCUGAGCCUUCCCAGAACAACAACUAUUUGCUCAGGACAUGAUGCUGAUACCGAAGAUGAUCCAUCCCUAGCAGAUUUGCCCCAGGCACUGGACCUCAGCCAGCAGCCUCACAGCUCAGGUCUCUCUUGCCUGUCACAGUGGAAGUCCGUGCUGAGCCCAGGUUCCGCAGCUCAGCCUUCCAGCUGCAGCAUCUCUGCUUCCUCCACAGGCAGCAGUCUCCAGGGUCACCAGGAGAGGGCGGAGCCUCGUGGUGGUUCUCUGGCCAAGGUCUCCUCCUCCCUGGAGCCGGUCGUCCCCCAGGAACCUUCCUCUGUGGUGGGGCUAGGACCUCGGCCCCAGUGGUCACCACAGCCUGUGUUCUCUGGGGGUGAUGCUUCUGGGCUAGGCAGGAGACGCCUCUCCUUCCAGGCUGAGUACUGGGCCUGUGUGCUGCCAGAUUCCCUGCCUCCAUCACCCGACCGCCACUCCCCUCUCUGGAACCCAAAUAAAGAGUAUGAAGAUCUGCUUGACUAUACUUACCCACUGAGGCCCGGGCCUCAGCUCCCAAAGCACCUUGAUAGCCGUGUGCCAGCUGACCCUGUCCUGCAGGACUCCGGGGUAGACCUGGAUAGCUUCUCUGUCUCUCCAGCAAGCACCCUCAAAUCACCUACUAAUGUCUCCCCCAACUGCCCACCAGCAGAGGCCACUGCCCUGCCAUUUUCUGGGCCCAGAGAGCCAAGCCUUAAGCAGUGGCCCUCCAGAGUACCCCAGAAACAGGGUGGCAUGGGCUUGGCAUCUUGGAGCCAACUUGCAUCUACCCCCAGAGCCCCAGGCAGUAGGGAUGCUCGUUGGGAGCGCAGAGAGCCAGCCCUGAGGGGUGCGAAGGACCGGCUGACUAUAGGCAAGCACCUUGAUAUGGGCUCUCCCCAGCUAAGGACACGGGACAGAGGGUGGCCCUCGCCCAGGCCAGAGAGGGAGAAGAGGACCAGCCAGAGUGCCCGGCGCCCUACCUGCACAGAGUCUAGGUGGAAAUCAGAAGAGGAAGUGGAAAGUGAUGACGAGUAUCUUGCCCUCCCCGCUCGGCUGACACAGGUUUCUAGCCUGGUUUCGUAUCUAGGAUCCAUUUCUACCUUGGUUACCCUGCCCACUGGGGAUAUCAAAGGGCAGAGCCCCUUGGAAGUGUCAGACAGUGAUGGGCCAGCUUCCUUCCCUUCAAGCUCCAGCCAAAGCCAGCUUCCCCCUGGAGCUGCCCUCCAAGGAUCUGGGGAUCCUGAGGGCCAGAAUCCCUGUUUCCUGCGCUCCUUCGUCCGUGCCCACGACUCCGCAGGGGAAGGCAGUCUGGGGAGCAGCCAGGCCCUCGGGGUCUCCUCUGGACUGCUGAAAACACGCCCCUCCUUGCCAGCUAGGUUGGACCGGUGGCCAUUCUCAGACCCAGAUGUUGAAGGGCAGCUUCCCAGGAAAGGAGGAGAACAGGGAAAAGAAUCACUGGUGCAAUGUGUGAAGACAUUUUGCUGUCAGCUGGAAGAGCUGAUCUGCUGGCUGUAUAAUGUUGCAGAUGUUACUGACCACGGGACUGCAGCCAGGUCCAAUCUUACAAGUCUCAAGUCUUCUCUGCAGCUUUACCGGCAAUUUAAGAAAGAUAUAGAUGAACAUCAGUCUCUGACGGAGAGUGUCUUACAGAAGGGGGAGAUUCUUCUUCAGUGCCUGUUGGAGAACACCCCAGUUUUAGAGGAUGUCCUUGGGAGGAUCGCAAAGCAGUCUGGUGAGCUGGAGAGCCACGCAGAUCGCCUGUAUGACUCUAUCUUGGCCUCUCUGGACAUGCUGGCUGGCUGCACCCUUAUCCCUGACAAAAAGCCCAUGGCGGCAAUGGAGCACCCAUGUGAAGGGGUUUAACCUGGCAUCUUCUCAGGCAGAGGUGCAACCUGUCGGCCAAACACUGGCUAGUGAGAAAAAAAACCUUCAAGAAGUCCUUGCAAGAGCCAUUCAACACUGAAGUCAAGGGGGAAACCUUCAAUAUACUAGCUUUAAAAUGCCUUUCUCCUCCCUGAAUGGAGGGCUGAGUUACUAUUUUUAUUUACAAUGAAUCCUUCCAAACUAAGGUUUUCCUUUUGGUGCUUCUCCACAAAGAGCGUGUAGCUUUGCAAUUUUUGAUAAAAUAAGACGUGUUGCCUUCCCCUCUAUCCCAUUAAAAAAGAGCAGAUAAAGCUCAAACUAUUCCACCUGGUAGGGUCAUUUACCAAGGGCUGGUAGGAGAUUCCGAAUACUCAAUAUUCUCAGGCAUGCAAGAGGACCUAAGAGACUGAAAAAAGUGAAUUGUUGGCCAGAAACCUUGGGUCUUUUCAUAAAAGGAAAUUUGGGCUUGUCAAUCCCUCUUUAAAGAUAUAGGUAGAAAGAAGAGAUUUUUAACCCUUUGUCUGCAAAAGAAAAAGGGUUAAAUGAAGCAUCUAUACAGAUGACUUUGGGAGAUUAUGACACCUUUUGCCAUCUUCAGGGCUUACGUCUUUACUUUCUUGGCUAACCAGUUUCUUAGAAGAAAAUGUGUCAGGGACUUGGGGAUCUACAGUCAUGCUUUAGCAUGGCUAUGGAGCUAAUUAUCAAGCUUAAAGGGUAACUUUGGGAGGACUCCUCCCUUCACUCCUAGUCUCCCUUGGAAGAGCAGUCCAGGCUCAGGGAAGGGAACGGAUAGGAUGACACAGUAAGUACAGAAACUGAAGCUGUCAAUAGUGAAGGAAAAAGGGGAAUUCUUCGUUGCUUUGGCAUUGACACAUAAGUACUUUGAUUAAAAAAAAAAAAAACUAUGGAUCAACCAUUCAAAGCAUCAAUUCUAUAGCUUUUUGCAGCAAGAUGAUCAGUUAUUGCUGGUAACUGCAGAUUCUACAGAAAAGCACUUUUAAAGUUCUGUUGGGCCAUGAAUGAACCUGGAAGGAGGAAAGCACAGUAACAAUGGAAACUAAAGUCCUAUUAUUAAUGUGACUUUUCUGCUUCAGAAUUUCUGAGACUUUAUAGUCACUGGAAAAUAGCCAUUAAAUUCUUUAAAGAUUAGCUCUUCAACAGUAGCUACACAUAAAAUGCAGUAUUUCAAGUGCCUGAUGCUGCUGUGGUAUGCUUUAUCAUAAUGCUUAAGGGCAUGAUCAAAAUUAAAAUGGCUUAUGAGUUUGCCAUAUUAAUCAUCUUAGUUCCAUACACACUGAGACUUUAAAAGGGAAAAACCACUCUAGCAAAUAAUUGUCAAUUAUAAACCUGUAUGUAAAACAUUCUUGAAAACCUAGAGUUGGUUAAAAAGGUAGAGAUGUCUGACGGCCUCUUCUUAAAUUGAUAUAUUUUACCUUCUCUUAGAUGUACAUUUAUAAGUAGGAACAUGUCCUUCCACUGAGUAUGUUACUGAAUAGCCCUUAGGAAAUUAAACCCAUUUAUUUACUAAUAUUUGACAGGCAUAGAAGUGUAUUAAUUAGCAUAAAAGUUGGAGAUGAAAACCCUAUAGAAACAAAUUGGCCAAUAUUAUACUAAUUGAAUGCAGAAUGUGGCAUUCUAUUCCCAUUCAACUAAUAAUCAGCUUCAACUGACAGGAAUUUGCACAGAAUGUUACACAAUACCCUGUUUCCCAAGAAAGUACUACCUUACCUAGAGAUGAUCUAAGAUAUUUUUGUUCAUCCUCUGAAUAAGGUGAGACUAAAGGGUGCUAACUCCCUGGACCUGGCUGUGAAUGCUACUGAAGAGUAUCAACACAACUGUUAAUUAUACCGCCGUGCUUUAAGUUUAAGACUUACCUUAAAACUCAAGCUGAAGGCUGGGCACGGUGGCUCAUGCCUGUAAUCCCAGCACUUUGGGAGGCCGAGGCGGGUGGAUCACAAGGUCAGGAGAUCGAGACCAUCCUGGCUAACACGGUGAAACCCCAUCUCUACUAAAAAUACAAAAAGAAAUUAGCCAGGCGUGGUGAUGGGCGCCUGUAGUCCCAGCUACUUGGGAGGCUGAGGCAUGAGAAUGGCAUGAACCCGGGAGGCGGAGCUUGCAGUGAGCUGAGAUGGCACCACUGCACUCCAGCCUGGGCAACAGAGUGAGACUCUUGUCUCAAAAAAAAAAAAUCAAGCUGAAAUUGUUUCAGCCUAGUAAGAUGCUGCCAGCAGCAUUUCUAUGAGCAAACAUGGCCAAAUUAGAGUCAAGUAGCUGAGCUUGCUAACUGCACUGUGAUGCCACACUGGAAUAACUUAGUAGUCCCUUAAAAUUAAUGGAAGUUAAAUCCACAGGGAAGUGAUGAUACUCAAAGCUGGAUCAGCAGUUUCAAGAUCUGGGUUCUUGGAGAUCCAUAGGUAAGCUCAGCAAAUGGAAGACGACGUCAACACGGCUAUUUUGAAGCUUAGGUGGGAAUGGAACACAAAGAAGGUUUGAGGUAAGAUAUGCUGGAAAGGCAAGAUGUAGGCUAAGGGAAAUUCAAUCCAAGGUCGAAGAAUAGGAAAUUACUGCUCAGACCACAAUGACUAUCAUUCUGAAAGGAUUUCACAGAGUGUGCAGCUGCUUAGAUUUAAGAACACUCUUCUUCACUAUGUAAACUAAUUUAUGGCAGCACCUUAUAUUUAGAACAAGUGGUAAUUCCCUUUACUAAGUGAACAGAUUAUUAAAACCUGUAGUAGCUUUGAACCGUUUGUACUUGAAAAUGGGGGUAUAAAGGGGUAUAUAUUUUUUCCAGAACCACAUUUAUUGGCGUAUACAUAGAAGCAAAUCUUAAGGCAUGCUGAAAUUUGUUGUAAAUCCCAAUCUUUACUGCCAUGGGGAAAAGAACGCUGGAAUUUUCCAAACUUAAGUCUGUAAAUAUGCUCAUCUUAAGUUCAUGUAAUGUUUCCGCUAACUCACCAAGAAUAAGCUGACAAUUUAAACAACUUUUACUGUGUAAAAAUGAAGUGCACGGCAUGGCAUCACAGUAUCUUGACAUUUGUUUUGUGUCAUUUAGCUACUUUAGAAAAUAGUUUCUGAACUCUUUCCCCCUUUAUACUGUAUUAAGGCAAAAACAAAACUUCUGAAGCAUUAAAGAUCUUCACCAAAAUAACUAUUGGUAACUUCAGGAAUUUGUCAGUUGCCUUAUGUGAGGAUGAAUAGAUCCACCAAGCACGCCUAUAAUACAAAGUAAACUAUGAUUUUUAUUGUGAAAUUUUCAUAGAUGGAAAAUUGAAUAUUCUGUCCAUUUCAUUUUACAAUUAUCUUACCACUUAUUUUUGUACCAUGUAUUUCAAUUGCCUGUUUAGUGAAAAAUAAAAAUUAAAAAAACCUA